GAAACAUUUGCUAGCCAGCUGAGUGACAGUGAUGGAUUCAAAACAUCAGUGUUUGAAGCUAAAUGAUGGUCACUUCAUGCCUGUCCUGGGAUUUGGCACCUAUGCACCUCCAGAGGUUCCGAGAAGUAAAGCUUUGGAGGUCACAAAAUUAGCAAUAGAAGCUGGGUUCCGCCAUAUAGAUUCUGCUCAUUUAUACAAUAAUGAGGAGCAGGUUGGACUGGCCAUCCGAAGCAAGAUUGCAGAUGGCAGUGUGAAGAGAGAAGACAUAUUCUACACUUCAAAGCUUUGGUCCACUUUUCAUCGACCAGAGUUGGUCCGACCAGCCUUGGAAAACUCACUGAAGAAAGCUCAAUUGGACUAUGUUGACCUCUAUCUUAUUCAUUCUCCAAUGUCUCUAAAGCCAGGUGAGGAACUUUCACCAACAGAUGAAAAUGGAAAAGUAAUAUUUGACAUAGUGGAUCUCUGUACCACCUGGGAGGCCAUGGAGAAGUGUAAGGAUGCAGGAUUGGCCAAGUCCAUUGGGGUGUCAAACUUCAACCGCAGGCAGCUGGAGAUGAUCCUCAACAAGCCAGGACUCAAGUACAAGCCUGUCUGCAACCAGGUAGAAUGUCAUCCGUAUUUCAACCGGAGUAAAUUGCUAGAUUUCUGCAAGUCGAAAGAUAUUGUUCUGGUUGCCUAUAGUGCUCUGGGAUCUCAACGAGACAAACGAUGGGUGGACCCGAACUCCCCGGUGCUCUUGGAGGACCCAGUCCUUUGUGCCUUGGCAAAAAAGCACAAGCGAACCCCAGCCCUGAUUGCCCUGCGCUACCAGCUGCAGCGUGGGGUUGUGGUCCUGGCCAAGAGCUACAAUGAGCAGCGCAUCAGACAGAACGUGCAGGUUUUUGAGUUCCAGUUGACUGCAGAGGACAUGAAAGCCAUAGAUGGCCUAGACAGAAAUCUCCACUAUUUUAACAGUGAUAGUUUUGCUAGCCACCCUAAUUAUCCAUAUUCAGAUGAAUAUUAACAUGGAGGGCUUUGCCUGAUGUCUACCAGAAGCCCUGUGUGUGGAUGGUGACGCAGAGGACGUCUCUAUGCCGGUGACUGGACAUAUCACCUCUACUUAAAUCCGUCCUGUUUAGCGACUUCAGUCAACUACAGCUGAGUCCAUAGGCCAGAAAGACAAUAAAUUUUUAUCAUUUUGAAAUAA